AUAGUUAGCUACUUUCAACUGGAAGCUACAACAUGGAUUUAUGGAAUCUGUCUUGGUUUCUGUUCUUGGAUGCUCUUCUCGUGAUUUCUGGCUUGGCAACUCCAGAAAACUUUGAUGUAGAUGGCGGAAUGGACCAGGACAUAUUUGAUAUCAAUGAAGGUUUGGGACUGGAUCUUUUUGAGGGUGACAUCAGACUUGAUAGGGCACAAAUUAGAAAUUCCAUCAUUGGAGAAAAGUAUAGAUGGCCUCAUACCAUUCCAUAUGUUCUAGAAGAUAGCUUGGAAAUGAAUGCUAAGGGAGUUAUCCUCAAUGCAUUUGAACGUUAUCGCCUUAAAACAUGUAUUGACUUUAAGCCUUGGGCUGGAGAAACAAACUAUAUAUCAGUGUUCAAGGGCAGUGGCUGCUGGUCUUCAGUAGGAAAUAGGCGGGUUGGGAAGCAAGAACUUUCCAUCGGGGCAAACUGUGACCGAAUAGCAACAGUUCAACACGAGUUCCUCCACGCUCUGGGAUUCUGGCAUGAGCAGUCGCGUUCUGACCGGGAUGACUAUGUCAGGAUAAUGUGGGACAGAAUUCUGUCAGGCAGAGAGCACAAUUUUAACACCUAUAGUGACGAUAUAUCAGAUUCCCUGAAUGUUCCCUAUGAUUACACUUCAGUAAUGCACUACAGUAAAACUGCAUUCCAAAAUGGAACAGAGCCGACAAUUGUCACAAGAAUCUCAGACUUUGAGGAUGUGAUCGGCCAACGAAUGGAUUUCAGUGACUCUGAUCUCCUAAAGUUGAAUCAACUGUAUAACUGCUCCUCUUCCUUGAGUUUUAUGGACUCGUGCAGUUUUGAACUGGAAAAUGUGUGUGGCAUGAUCCAAAGUUCAGGAGAUAAUGCUGACUGGCAACGGGUUUCACAGGUUCCCAGGGGGCCAGAGAGUGAUCACUCCAACAUGGGCCAGUGCCAAGGUUCUGGUUUCUUCAUGCAUUUCGAUAGCAGCUCUGUAAAUGUGGGGGCCACAGCAGUGCUGGAAAGUAGAACGCUGUACCCUAAAAGAGGAUUUCAGUGCCUGCAAUUUUACUUAUAUAACAGUGGCAGUGAAAGUGAUCAACUGAACAUCUAUAUCAGGGAGUAUUCUGCAGACAAUGUGGAUGGCAAUUUAACCCUUGUGGAAGAAAUAAAAGAAAUACCCACUGGGAGCUGGCAACUUUAUCAUGUAACAUUGAAAGUGACCAAGAAGUUUAGAGUGGUGUUUGAAGGACGCAAAGGCUCUGGUGCAUCACUGGGUGGUCUGUCUAUUGAUGACAUCAAUCUUUCGGAAACACGGUGCCCUCAUCAUAUCUGGCAUAUAAGGAAUUUCACACAGUUCAUUGGCAGCCCAAAUGGAACUCUGUAUAGCCCUCCAUUUUACUCUUCUAAAGGUUAUGCCUUUCAGAUUUACUUAAAUCUAGCCCAUGUGACUAAUGCAGGGAUAUAUUUCCACUUGAUCUCUGGAGCCAAUGAUGAUCAAUUACAGUGGCCAUGUCCUUGGCAACAAGCCACAAUGACACUUUUGGAUCAAAAUCCUGACAUUCGACAGCGUAUGUCCAAUCAGCGGAGUAUAACUACAGACCCAUUUAUGACCACCGAUAAUGGAAACUAUUUCUGGGACAGGCCUUCUAAAGUGGGAACAGUGGCUUUGUUCUCUAAUGGAACUCAGUUUAGAAGAGGUGGGGGCUAUGGAACCAGUGCCUUUAUAACCCACGAAAGGCUGAAAAGCAGAGAUUUUAUAAAAGGAGAUGAUGUUUAUAUCCUACUGACAGUGGAAGACAUAUCUCACCUCAACUCUACACAAAUCCAGCUAACACCAGCCCCUAGUGUUCAAGACCUCUGCUCAAAAACCACCUGUAAAAAUGACGGUGUCUGCACUGUUCGAGAUGGCAAAGCUGAGUGCAGGUGCCAGUCAGGGGAAGACUGGUGGUACAUGGGAGAAAGGUGUGAAAAGAGAGGCUCCACCCGAGACACCAUAGUCAUUGCUGUUUCAUCUACUGUUGCUGUGUUUGCCUUGAUGCUGAUCAUCACCCUUGUCAGUGUCUAUUGCACCAGGAAGAAAUAUCGUGAAAGGAUGAGCUCAAAUCGACCAAAUUUGACUCCGCAAAAUCAGCAUGCUUUUUGAAGAUUAACUCGACAAUAUGGCCAGCUAAUGAAAUUAAAAAGGAUUCUUCAUCAUGGAUUUCGCCUAAGUGAUAUUACAGCCACCUCAUUCUUCUAAAAGUGGAUAUUUUUCUGUAAAUAGCUGGAAAUAUUAUAAAUCACUAUUUUGGUCAAAGUCAAA